AGCGCAGGCUGAUAACCGCACGGAACUUCCCAGGCACCCUGUGUGGCCGCACUGCUCCCUCUGGCCCAACCAUGCCUCUGUCCAGCCACCUGCUGCCCGCCUUGGUCCUGUUCCUGGCAGGGUCCUCAGGCUGGGCCUGGGUCCCCAACCACUGCAGGAGCCCUGGCCAGGCCGUGUGCAACUUCGUGUGUGACUGCAGGGACUGCUCAGAUGAGGCCCAGUGUGGUUACCACGGGGCCUCGCCCACCCUGGGCGCCCCCUUCGCCUGUGACUUCGAGCAGGACCCCUGCGGCUGGCGGGACAUUAGUACCUCAGGCUACAGCUGGCUCCGAGACAGGGCAGGGGCCGCACUGGAGGGUCCUGGGCCUCACUCAGACCACACACUGGGCACCGACUUGGGCUGGUACAUGGCCGUUGGAACCCACCGAGGGAAAGAGGCAUCCACCGCAGCCCUGCGCUCGCCAACCCUGCGAGAGGCAGCCUCCUCUUGCAAGCUGAGGCUCUGGUACCACGCGGCCUCUGGAGAUGUGGCUGAACUGCGGGUGGAGCUGACCCAUGGCGCAGAGACCCUGACCCUGUGGCAGAGCACAGGGCCCUGGGGCCCUGGCUGGCAGGAGUUGGCAGUGACCACAGGCCGCAUCCGGGGUGACUUCCGAGUGACCUUCUCUGCCACCCGAAAUGCCACCCACAGGGGCGCUGUGGCUCUAGAUGACCUAGAGUUCUGGGACUGUGGUCUGCCCACCCCCCAGGCCAACUGUCCCCCGGGACACCACCACUGCCAGAACAAGGUCUGCGUGGAGCCCCAGCAGCUGUGCGACGGGGAAGACAACUGCGGGGACCUGUCUGAUGAGAACCCACUCACCUGUGGCCGCCACAUAGCCACCGACUUUGAGACAGGCCUGGGCCCAUGGAACCGCUCGGAAGGCUGGUCCCGGAACCACCGCGCUGGUGGUCCUGAGCGCCCCUCCUGGCCACGCCGUGACCACAGCCGGAACAGUGCACAGGGCUCCUUCCUGGUCUCCGUGGCCGAGCCUGGCACCCCUGCUAUACUCUCCAGCCCCGAAUUCCAAGCCUCAGGCACCUCCAACUGCUCGCUGGUCUUCUAUCAGUACCUGAGUGGGUCUGAGGCUGGCUGCCUCCAGCUGUUCCUGCAGACUCUGGGGCCCGGCGCCCCCCGGGCCCCCGUCCUGCUGCGGAGGCGCCGAGGGGAGCUGGGGACCGCCUGGGUCCGAGACCGUGUUGACAUCCAGAGCGCCUACCCCUUCCAGAUCCUCCUGGCCGGGCAGACAGGCCCGGGGGGCGUCGUGGGUCUGGACGACCUCAUCCUGUCUGACCACUGCAGACCAGUCUCGGAGGUGUCCACCCUGCAGCCGCUGCCUCCUGGGCCCCGGGCCCCAGCCCCCCAGCCCCUGCCGCCCAGCUCGCGGCUCCAGGAUUCCUGCAAGCAGGGGCAUCUUGCCUGCGGGGACCUGUGUGUGCCCCCGGAACAACUGUGUGACUUCGAGGAGCAGUGCGCAGGGGGCGAGGACGAGCAGGCCUGUGGCACCACAGACUUUGAGUCCCCCGAGGCUGGGGGCUGGGAGGACGCCAGCGUGGGGCGGCUGCAGUGGCGGCGUGUCUCAGCCCAGGAGAGCCAGGGGUCCAGUGCAGCUGCUGCUGGGCACUUCCUGUCUCUGCAGCGGGCCUGGGGGCAGCUAGGCGCUGAGGCCCGGGUCCUCACACCCCUCCUUGGCCCUUCUGGCCCCAGCUGUGAACUCCACCUGGCUUAUUAUUUACAGAGCCAGCCCCGAGAGGUCUCCUGUAACUUUGAGCGGGACACAUGCAGCUGGUACCCAGGCCACCUCUCAGACACACACUGGCGCUGGGUGGAGAGCCGCGGCCCUGACCACGACCACACCACAGGCCAAGGCCACUUUGUGCUCCUGGACCCCACAGACCCCCUGGCCUGGGGCCACAGUGCCCACCUGCUCUCCAGGCCCCAGGUGCCAGCAGCACCCACGGAGUGUCUCAGCUUCUGGUACCACCUCCAUGGGCCCCAGAUUGGGACUCUGCGCCUAGCCAUGAGACGGGAAGGGGAGGAGACACACCUGUGGUCGCGGUCAGGCACCCAGGGCAACCGCUGGCACGAGGCCUGGGCCACCCUUUCCCACCAGCCUGGCUCCCAUGCCCAGUACCAGCUGCUGUUCGAGGGCCUCCGGGACGGAUACCACGGCACCAUGGCGCUGGACGAUGUGGCCGUGCGGCCGGGCCCCUGCUGGGCCCCUAAUUACUGCUCCUUUGAGGACUCAGACUGCGGCUUCUCCCCUGGAGGCCAAGGUCUCUGGAGGCGGCAGGCCAAUGCCUCGGGCCAUGCUGCCUGGGGCCCCCCAACAGACCAUACCACUGAGACAGCCCAAGGGCACUACAUGGUGGUGGACACAAGCCCAGACGCACUACCCCGGGGCCAGACGGCCUCCCUGACCUCCAAGGAGCACAGGCCCCUGGCCCAGCCUGCUUGUCUGACCUUCUGGUACCACGGGAGCCUCCGCAGCCCAGGCACCCUGCGGGUCUACCUGGAGGAGCGCGGGAGGCACCAGGUGCUCAGCCUCAGUGCCCACGGCGGGCUUGCCUGGCGCCUGGGCAGCAUGGACGUGCAGGCCGAGCGAGCCUGGAGGGUGGUGUUUGAGGCAGUGGCCGCAGGCGUGGCACACUCCUACGUGGCUCUGGAUGAUCUGCUCCUCCAGGACGGGCCCUGCCCUCAGCCAGGUUCCUGUGAUUUUGAGUCUGGCCUGUGUGGCUGGAGCCACCUGGCCUGGCCCGGCCUGGGCGGAUACAGCUGGGACUGGGGCGGGGGAGCCACCCCCUCUCGUUACCCCCAGCCCCCUGUGGACCACACCCUGGGCACAGAGGCAGGCCACUUUGCCUUCUUUGAAACUGGCGUGCUGGGCCCCGGGGGCCGGGCCGCCUGGCUGCGCAGCGAGCCUCUGCCGGCCACCCCAGCCUCCUGCCUCCGCUUCUGGUACCACAUGGGUUUUCCUGAGCACUUCUACAAGGGGGAGCUGAAGGUACUGCUGCACAGUGCUCAGGGCCAGCUGGCUGUGUGGGGCGCAGGCGGGCAUCGGCGGCACCAGUGGCUGGAGGCCCAGGUGGAGGUAGCCAGUGCCAAGGAGUUCCAGAUCGUGUUUGAAGCCACUCUGGGCGGCCAGCCAGCCCUGGGGCCCAUUGCCCUGGAUGACGUGGAGUAUCUGGCUGGGCAGCAUUGCCAGCAGCCUGCCCCCAGCCCGGGGAACACAGCCGCACCCGGGUCUGUGCCAGCUGUGGUUGGCAGUGCCCUCCUAUUGCUCAUGCUCCUGGUGCUGCUGGGACUUGGGGGACGGCGCUGGCUGCAGAAGAAGGGGAGCUGCCCCUUCCAGAGCAACACAGAGGCCACAGCCCCUGGCUUUGACAACAUCCUUUUCAAUGCGGAUGGUGUCACCCUCCCGGCAUCUGUCACCAGUGAUCCGUAGACCACCCCAGACAAGGCCCCGCUUCCUCACGUGACAUCCAGCACUUGGUCAGACCCUAGCCAGGGACCGGACACCUGCCCCGCCCAGGCUGGGACAGGCUGCAGGUCUCAGGAUAUGCUGAGGCCUGGGCGUUCCCUGCCCUGUGCUGACUCUGUUGCUCUGUGAAUAAACACCCUGGCCCAUGAGGGCAGCCCAA